CACCUUUAUUUUCUGUCUUUCAACUGGCAAGAGUCAUUUUGACCAGCAGGUUAAUCAACUCUAAGACAGAUCCUCACGCAAAGAGGCAACUGAAAGGAUGAAAUCACUGACUUGGAUCUUGGGCCUUUGGGCUCUUGCAGCGUGUUUCACACCUGGUGAGAGUCAAAGAGGCCCCAGGGGACCAUAUCCACCUGGACCACUGGCUCCUCCUCCUCCACCAUGUUUUCCUUUUGGAACAGGAUUUGUUCCACCACCCCAUCCUCCACCCUAUGGUCCAGGGAGAUUUCCACCACCCCUUUCUCCACCCUAUGGUCCAGGGAGAAUCCCACCAUCCCCUCCUCCACCCUAUGGUCCAGGGAGAAUUCAAUCACACUCUCUUCCUCCUCCUUAUGGCCCAGGUUAUCCACAGCCACCUUCCCAACCAAGACCCUAUCCACCUGGACCUCCAUUUUUCCCUGUAAAUUCUCCAACUGAUCCUGCCCUCCCUACUCCUGCACCCUAAAUACAGACAACUGCAACAGGUGCCACCACCCACAAAAGACAACACUACCCUCGUAACUACUGCUUCUACUACCCAAAAAUAAGAAUUUCAACACUACUUCCAAGAGACUUUUAGAUAAAAUCACUUCCAUUUUUGGAUGAGAAUAAAGAUUUCCAAAGCACUGA